CUGGGGCGCGGCCGCCUGUCUGCACAGACAGCACCAUGUCGCUCAUGGUCGUCAGCAUGGCGUGUGUUGGGUUCUUCUUGCUGCAGGGGGCCUGGCCACAUGAGGGAGUCCACAGAAAACCUUCCCUCCUGGCCCACCCAGGUCCCCUGGUGAAAUCAGAAGAGACAGUCAUCCUGCAAUGUUGGUCAGAUGUCAGGUUUGAGCACUUCCUUCUGCACAGAGAGGGGAAGUAUAAGGACACUUUGCACCUCAUUGGAGAGCACCAUGAUGGGGUCUCCAAGGCCAACUUCUCCAUCGGUCCCAUGAUGCAAGACCUUGCAGGGACCUACAGAUGCUACGGUUCUGUUACUCACUCCCCCUAUCAGUUGUCAGCUCCCAGUGACCCUCUGGACAUCGUCAUCACAGGUCUAUAUGAGAAACCUUCUCUCUCAGCCCAGCCGGGCCCCACGGUUUUGGCAGGAGAGAGCGUGACCUUGUCCUGCAGCUCCCGGAGCUCCUAUGACAUGUACCAUCUAUCCAGGGAGGGGGAGGCCCAUGAACGUAGGUUCUCUGCAGGGCCCAAGGUCAACGGAACAUUCCAGGCCGACUUUCCUCUGGGCCCUGCCACCCACGGAGGAACCUACAGAUGCUUCGGCUCUUUCCGUGACUCUCCCUAUGAGUGGUCAAACUCGAGUGACCCACUGCUUGUUUCUGUCACAGGAAACCCUUCAAAUAGUUGGCCUUCACCCACUGAACCAAGCUCCAAAACCGAUACUCCUACAGCGAAAGGGAUCUGGGUCCAACACAGGGCUCAGUGAAAUCUCUUCAUCUCUCAUUUUAUGGAGCUGAGACUUCCUACAAGCUAGAAGAAUGAUUGCCAAUCUGACAUCCUUCUCAGGAAAAAUGCAAUGUUUGUUCUGCCUGCAUUCCUAACUGGAGGAUAAAUUCCUGGAGACUUGAGAGAGGGAAGGGAAGGGAACAUCUGAUGAGGGCGAGGUGUUUUAGAGAAGUUCCACUUGCCAAGGAAUGAGCUCCUAUAGGUCAUGAAGCAACCCUGGCUGACUCAGCAGAGAAAGAGCCUUGCUGUAACAGAGAACAGAGCUCAUGCACGCACACUUCGACUCACUGACUCAUUCAGCCACGGCCCCAUGCUCAGGCUGUGCACUGUGGAAGCUUUUCCUAUUGUUGCCAUAACAAAUUUCCACAAGAUUCGUGGGUGAAAACAAAACGGUUUUUUAAUUAUCUUACAGUGCUGUAGCUCAAAGUAUGAAGUGCAUCUCACUGGGCUAAAAUCAAGGUGACAGCAAGGCUGCCUUCCCUCUGAGGAUUCCAGGCAAGAAUCUGCUUCUCACUUUUCUCAGCUUCUAGAGGCUCCCACAUUCCUUCGCUCCUGGUCCCCUUCCUCCUUCCUCAAAGCCCACAAAGACUGGUCACAUCUCACAUGGCAUCACUCAGACCCUUCUUCCUUACCACACCUCUUUCUCUGAAUGCUGCUCUCCCUUCUUCCUCAUCUUUUGAAAACUUGGGGAUUCUAUUGGGUUCACCAAGAUGAAAAUCCAUCAUAAUCUCCCGGAAAUCAUUCAGGAUACCCUUGUUUUAAGUUCAGCUGAUUAGCAACCAUAAUUCCAUCUGCAAUCUUCAUUCCUCCUUUCCAUGUAAAAUAAGAUAUUCACAAGCUAUGGAGGCUAGGACAGGGACAUUUUGGGGUGGGACAGCAUUCUCCUGCCUUCCACAAACAGUGAACAAGAUGCAUUUGGCCUCUGCUCUUUGGACACUGAUAUU